AUGGUGCGGAGUCUGCGGGGGGAGGGCGGGUGUUCAACGGGCUCCAAAGGAAGGAGCUCGUGGCUGACGCCUGAGCCUCCAUGUUAUGCCUCCCCCGCCCAAAUCCCAUUUCCACGCCAAAUAUUAUUAAAUUUGGUUUCUCCUCCUCCUCCUCACGCAAGUUCUCUUUCUCUCGCCAGCACCUCCCCCACGUUUUCCUGCUCUCCACCAGCCGGGCCGGACUCCUCCCGGCCCCCAGCGGCGCGCUUCCCUGGCCCGCUGGCCCGCGCCGCCCUCCGCGCCUGCGGCUGCGCGCACUGGGCUGCCUCCGGGGCUGGCAGGGCAGCGGCGGCCGCGGCGGCGGCGGGGCCGGGAGCGAGCGGCGGCGGCGGCGGCGGCGUGGGGAGUGGCGUGGAGCGGUGCCUGGGGCUGCAGCAGCACGGGGACCCGGCAGUAGAAAGCCCCGGGGACAAGGAAGGAAGGCUUGGCCGCCAAAUCCCUGAGCAACCGUUCUUCUUGGAUUUUGGGGGGAGCCUGCCCCCCCCACUUCGUCUUCAAACGCCCCCAUCUCACCCCCCCACAGCCCCGGCCGCUGACGGGAGGAGGCGGCGGCGCCAGCGGGGGGCUGAGGGGCGCCGCCAUGCCUCUCCCGCGGUGAAGCGCCCCGGCCGUGAGGAGCCGCUGGUCUCCCCGGUGAUGUUCCCCAGGCGGCAGGCGAAAGCGACUCACUCGAGCCCUGGGGUAAAGGCCUAGCUUAUCCAGCUUCCUUCCUCCUCCUCCUCCUCUUCCCCUCCCCCUCCCCCUCCUCCUCUCCCCCCUUCGUCCUCCCCUCCCG